GGCCCCCUAGCGUCGCGCAGGGUCGGGGACUGCGCGGCGGUGCCAGGCCGGGCGUGGGCGAGAGCACGAACGGGCUGCCUGCGGGCUGAGAGCGUCGAGCUGUCACCAUGGGUGAUCACGCUUGGAGCUUCCUAAAGGACUUCCUGGCCGGGGGCGUCGCCGCUGCCGUCUCCAAGACCGCGGUCGCCCCCAUCGAGAGGGUCAAACUGCUGCUGCAGGUCCAGCAUGCCAGCAAACAGAUCAGUGCUGAGAAGCAGUACAAAGGGAUCAUUGAUUGUGUGGUGAGAAUCCCUAAGGAGCAGGGCUUCCUCUCCUUCUGGAGGGGUAACCUGGCCAACGUGAUCCGUUACUUCCCCACCCAAGCUCUCAACUUCGCCUUCAAGGACAAGUACAAGCAGCUCUUCUUAGGGGGUGUGGAUCGGCAUAAGCAGUUCUGGCGCUACUUUGCUGGUAACCUGGCGUCCGGUGGGGCCGCUGGGGCCACCUCCCUUUGCUUUGUCUACCCGCUGGACUUUGCUAGGACCAGGUUGGCUGCUGAUGUGGGCAAGGGCGCCGCCCAGCGUGAGUUCCAUGGUCUGGGCGACUGUAUCAUCAAGAUCUUCAAGUCUGAUGGCCUGAGGGGGCUCUACCAGGGUUUCAACGUCUCUGUCCAAGGCAUCAUUAUCUAUAGAGCUGCCUACUUCGGAGUCUAUGAUACUGCCAAGGGGAUGCUGCCUGACCCCAAGAACGUGCACAUUUUUGUGAGCUGGAUGAUUGCCCAGAGUGUGACGGCAGUCGCAGGGCUGGUGUCCUACCCCUUUGACACUGUUCGUCGUAGAAUGAUGAUGCAGUCCGGCCGGAAAGGGGCCGAUAUUAUGUACACGGGGACAGUUGACUGCUGGAGGAAGAUUGCAAAAGACGAAGGAGCCAAGGCCUUCUUCAAAGGUGCCUGGUCCAAUGUGCUGAGAGGCAUGGGCGGUGCUUUUGUAUUGGUGUUGUAUGAUGAGAUCAAAAAAUAUGUCUAAUGUAAUUAAAACACAAGUUCACAGAUUUACAGUGAACUUGAUCUACAAGUUCACAGAUCCAUUGUGUGGUUUAAUAGACUAUUCCUAGGGGAAGUAAAAAGAUCUGGGAUAAAACCAGACUGAAAGGAAUACCUCAGAAGAGAUGCUUCAUUGAGUGUUCAUUAAACCACACAUGUAUUUUGUAUUUAUUUUACAUUUAAAUUCCCACAGCAAAUAGAAAAUAAUUUAUCAUACUUGUACAAUUAACUGAAGAAUUGAUAAUAACUGAAUGUGAAACAUCAAUAAAGACCACUUAAUGCACGCUUUCUAUUUUAUUGAACUCUUAUUAACUGUAAAAUGCAUUUUUAAAAGAUCAAAAAUGCAUAUUUUCUAGCAUGAUUCAUGUAUCAGUCAGCAGCCAAGCUUCUAAAUGCCAGAUAUUAUAUUGAGAAUGUAUUAUAUGAGAACGUACAAUGCUUAAAGUUCCGGUUUUCAAACUUAGGCAGGUCAUAUUCUAUCUAUCUUAUCCAGCAUUACUGUAGGCUAGAAAGUGAUAAUGGCUUUCAUAAUCCUGCCUUGUCUUAGGCACUUUCCUGCAGUCUUUAGAAAUUCUAAGAUUCUGCUAAAAGUUUUAAAUCACAAUCUGGAGAAUUUUCUAUGAUUAGGAAGUGCUCUGUUUUCAUCCCUUUAGAUAACUGUGACACCUAGAAUUUUAUGUUAAGUAGAGAGUAUUCAUUGAAAAUCAAGGCCAGGUGCAGUGGCUCACACCUGUCACCCCAGCACUUUGGGAGGCAGAGGUGGGCGUAUCACUUCAGGCCAGGAGUUUGAGACCAGCCUGGCCAACCGAGCGAAACCCCAUCUCUAAUAAAAAUACAAAAAAUUAGCUGGGUGUGGUGGCGCACACCUGUAAUCCCAACUACUCAGGAGGCUGAGGCAUCAGAAUCACUUGAACCCGAGAGGCAGAGGUUGCAGUGAGCUGAGAUGGCAUGCCACCACAUCCAUCCUAAGCGACAGGGCAAGACUCUGUCUCAAAAAAAAAAAAAAGAAAGAAAAUCAGUUGUCUUAGUUUAAGCUACUAUAACAAGGUACUGUAGACUGAUGGCUUAUAAGCAACAGAAACUUAUUUCUCAGUUCUGUAGUCUGGAGGUCCAAGAUCAAGGUGACACUGUGGUCAGGUUCUGAUGAGGGCCCUCUUCUGGGUUAUAAACUACGGACUUCUUGUAUCCUUACAUGGCAGAAAGAGCGACAGAGCUCUCUGUAGUCCCUUUUAUAAGCUCACUAAUCCCAUUCAUGAGGGCCCUACCCUCAUGACCCAAUUACCUCCCAAAUGCCCCUCCUCCAAACACCACCACUUUGGGGGUUAAGAUUUCAACAGAUGAAUUUUGAAGGGACACAAACAUUCAGUCCAUAGCAUCACUUAUCAAGCUAGUAUUUAAUACCUCUUAGGCCCCGUGGAAGGGAAAAUAGAUAGGAACCUGCCCUGAAAGAUGCUUCAGUUGGGGAGAAAAGGUGAAAUUCCAUUGUUAGACAAUUUGUUUAAGACAAUACAUCUUGCUUGAGAAGGAAUAGAAGGGAAAUGAAAUGGGGGGAGGGAGUGGUAGGAGAUGGAGGCUUUGAAAGAAAAUAACCAGAUUUAGAAACAUGGGUAUAGAAAGCAUCCUCCAGUACUUCUGUAACAAUUUAUCAAGACCUACAGGAAGUCAGUUUUGGAUUUGCUCCUCCGAGAUUUGCGAGCCAGAGGAAAAUACUUAGACUAUCAGGUUGGAAAGUUCACACUUGGACCAGGAAAAGACCAAGCAGUUGCUAUAGUCUCCUGGAUUGUGACUAAUCUGGAGGAAGCAAGUCCCUGUAUCCUUGGCAAAGCUUGAAAGGCAGGCAAAUGUCUUCUCUGUGUUUUCUGACAGGUGGUUGGGUGGUGGGGGUUGGUCUCUGUACCUCCUGUUCUUUACCUUGCUUACCAAGCCCUUCCACCGACUCACUCCUGCCUCCCCAGCUAAAAAUUGGCUGUGUUGCUUUUACCACAGUUACCAAGGUCUGAGUUUUAUAAAAUCCAGGAUCACAUCUGACCUCACCUGGUAGAUAUCUAGGCCAAUAAAGUCUAAAGGGCUAAAAAGAAGGUACCUCUCCAUCCUGUCUCCUCGAGGCCAGGCAGCACAUGUGCAGUUAAGAGGCCUCCUGGAUCCAUUGUCCUCCUGUUGCUUUUCGUUCUAAGUGAUCCAAACUCUAUUGCUGAUAGGGAAUAAAAGCAGGGCAGGCUAGUAGUGGGCAAGUGCUUUGAUGGAGCGUAUCUCCAAGCAGGGCCCAAGUUUAGGAGGAGGAAGACCUGAUACAAUGAAUGAACAGUGCGUCCUCCCAACCCAACCAAGAAGUGUAAUUGUGUUCCGUCUUUAACCCUGGCAUGGAAUGGGGAGGGAAGAGGCAUGGACAUUUAUUACAUAGUGCACAUUAUCUACAUUCUCUGCAUGUGACCCAGAUGUCAGCCCUUCCGCUUCCUGCGAAGGUUACCUCUAAUGCACGUUGCCCCAGGCCCUGCUGAGCUAGUUCCUCACCGCAGCUACUUAACUCACCAUGAAUUCCUAGAACCCUCAGCCUCUGAGAGUGCUGGGAUCUGGCGGGAGAACAGGCAGUACUUCCCUCACUAACCUACCCGCACGCCAUACCAUCAUUGUGCAAAGCUGCCUCAUGCUGGAAGGUCUGGUUUACGUAAAAGUGACAAGUUGGAAUUGAGCGUCCGACUCUCGGGUACCUGCCCCAGGCAUUUCUCAUCAGCCCCAUUUCCCACACAGCUCUCUCCUAGGCGCAGCCCUCCUUCACCACCACCACCCCCACCCCAAUCACCUUUAGGUAUUUUCUCCCCUAAAGCCUCACCUGUUGGCAUUUUACAUCUUUUUAAGACCUUAUUUUGUAUUUUAAAUGUAUGAGAAAAAUUAUGGAGGAUGAUGCAAGAUGAGUGAGUCCAUAAUGGUAAUAAUUGGACACUAAAAACAAUGAAAACUUGUCUCAAGUAUUUGUGUUGAAAUCUCAAUUAACUGGGCGACUGCUCCCGUUCCAUUUUAUUCUGUAAAAUAUGUGGCAUCCUUUGUGUUGAGGCGGCAUUUACUAAACACCCCCAAGGUGCAAGGCUGCAAGAGAAUCGAGCGCCGCAAGGCGAGCUUAUCUUCCACACCUGGUACAGUGCCCAGGACAGAGAAGGUGUUUAGCAAGUUUCUGCUGAAUGGAAGAGUGAGCGAGAAGGGAAAGUGCAUCUAAAAAGCACAGGGAACCUACAAAAUAUUUGGGAAAGGGUUUCAUCAGUUCGGGUGAAAUCUUGAACGUGCAAAGCACCAUGGGGGUGGCUGGACAGGCUUGUUGGAGUCGUAUAAUGCAAUGAAUAAAAACUUACGGCUGCCUUAAAUGCAAAUGUCAAGCCCUUAAAUAAAAUUUAACAAAGUC